AGGCUGGGUCCAGAGCUCGCGGCUUCCGGGAGGCGCCCGAAGUCGGAGAAAUACAGCGCGGCCACCCCGGGAGCAGCAGCCUUUGCCCGCACCGCCGCCCGCAGGGCCCUGAACCGCCGGCAAGGGCGCGGGCCGGGCGCGGCGCCGGCUCCUCCUCCUGCCGCGUCCGGCGCGGAGCAGCGGAGAGCGGCGGGCUCGGCAGCCGGCGCCCGGGCCGCGGAACUGAUGAGCCGCGGCGGCUGAGGGCCCGGCCGGCCUCUGCCCGCCUCUGCCCGGCGCCCGAGCGGGGCCGCAGCGCCCGGGGCGCGGGGUCCGGCGGGUGACAUGGGGGCGGCCUGACGCACCCGGAGCCGCCGAGCGCUCUCUCUCGAGCCGCGGGCCCUCCUCGGCGGCAGCGGCUGCAGGCGCCUGGCCCGGCGCGCUGUGCCCGGGGCGCCCGCGGAGCCUCCGCCGCGCUCUAUGCGCCUCUGCGGGAGCCGCGGGCCCGGGCCAUGGCCAUAGACCGGCGGCGCGAGGCGGCGGGCGGCGGGCCUGGGCGGCAGCCGGCCCCGGCCGAGGAGAACGGCUCCCUGCCGCCCGGGGACGCGGCGGCCUCGGCGCCCCUCGGGGGACGCGCGGGCCCCGGCGGCGGCGCGGAGAUCCAGCCGCUGCCCCCACUGCAUCCUGGAGGCGGCCCGCACCCGAGCUGCUGCUCCGCGGCUGCGGCCCCGAGCCUCUUGUUGCUGGACUAUGACGGGUCGGUGCUGCCCUUCCUCGGGGGCCUGGGCGGGGGCUAUCAGAAGACCCUCGUGCUGCUCACCUGGAUCCCGGCGCUGUUCAUCGGCUUCAGCCAGUUCUCGGACUCGUUCCUCCUGGACCAGCCCAACUUCUGGUGCCGCGGGGCCGGCAAAGGCACCGAGCUGGCAGGGGUCACCACCACAGGCCGGGGCGGGGACAUGGGCAACUGGACCAGCCUCCCCACCACCCCCUUCGCCACUGCCCCCUGGGAGGCUGCGGGCAACCGGAGCAACAGCAGCGGCGCGGACGGAGGCGACACACCACCCCUGCCAUCCCCUCCGGACAAGGGGGACAACGCCUCCAACUGUGACUGCCGCGCAUGGGACUACGGCAUCCGCGCCGGCCUCGUCCAGAACGUGGUCAGCAAGUGUUGUCAGCAGCAGGAAACUGGAGCUCUCCCGUGGGACACAGACACCAAGCGCUGGAGGCCGGAGCUGAACGCUUCUUCAAAGUCUCACAGCCAGCCUACCCUCAAAGCCUGAGUGAUUGUGGAAGGAGCCAGCGUUCACUCAGCAGAGGAACAGAGCUUUCCUGCCGCAGGCUCUCAGUGAAGAUCCAGGGAGCAGAGGCGUGGGCAAGGAGCACUGGGCUCAGAUGCAGGAGAACCGGUUUGAACCCUAGCACUACCGCCUCUACACUGAGGAACCUUGGGGAUUACUCAGCCCCCUGGAACCUAAUUUCCAAGGUAGAGAUGACACCUAUAGCAUAAAGCUUUGUGGGGAUUACAGAAAAUGAUGGAUGUGCCGCUCCCUUUCAGCAGAGUGUGUGCUUUGAGAUACGCAUUUAAUCUGAGCCCUUUUCUGCAAAGAGCUCCCAGUGGAGCUCAGAGGACAGUCAUGUAACCAACAACUACAAUGCAUUAUACAACCACCUGCAAUCCCCCAACCAUUAACUCUAGACCUCUAAAACAGAAGUAUGGAAGCUCAUAGGAAAUGACCGAGGUCAGCCCUGGCAAAUGGCGGUCUUUGUGGUCCCCAGCUGGCCACCUGAGCUGUGGACACGUUUGUUUGCCUUGUGCCCUCACUUUCAGAACCCCUCCUCCUUUGGCCUCAUAUUGUCCCUAGCUAUUUGACAUCUCCUCAUUUAGGAGUGCUUCUCAGGUGCUCUCAAAUGACCUCUUUUUCAAAAUUUCCUCUCUAUUCCUACUUUCCAAAACCAAAAUAUCUGGGCAGCUAAUUUUAGCUAAGAGAUGAAAGCAGUUCACACUAAGGUACGAAGGACUGAUAGGAUUGACCCUACUCUUUCUGAGCUCAUCCAUAACUUCAACCUGUUAAUUGAGGACUGGCCAAUAGCCCACAAACUUCAUGCCCACCCAUAGAUGGUUUUGAAAGGCUGAACCUUUAACAGCCCUCCCUCCCUUUCUCCCUUCCCUGUCCCCUGCAGAGCCAGGCUUAGGAAUUUGGUCCUCCUUUUCUGUGAUCCUUGAUCAGGAUAUUUCUAACAACAGUAGCAUCAACCGAAAGCCCCAAAUAAGGUUUGAUUGAGUUAACAUUUUCAUUGCAUUUUAAGUCUAGUCCUGAUUAACAUUCCACUCUGUGACAUGGGUGCAGGGUGUGUCCUCACAGGACCUGCCCCCACGCCCAUCUCACUCAGUGUCCAGUCCAGGUGCAGGUAUCCCUCCUGGAAGCCUCCCUUGAGCCUGCCCCACAUUUUUAAACCCUCACACAUGCUGUGUUUUCUUUUUCUUUCUUUCUUUUUUUUUUUUUUUUUUUGAGACGGAGUUUUGCUCUUGUUGCCCAGGCUGGAGUGCAAUGAUGCAAUCUCGGCUCACCACAACCUCCGCUUCCCAGGUUGAAGUGAUUCUCCUGCCUCAGCCUCCCAAGUAGCUGGGAUUACAGGUGCGUGCCACCACACCCAGCUAAUUUUGUAUUUUUAGUAGAGACGGGGUUUCUCCAUGUUGGUCAGGCUGGUCUCAAACUUCCCACCUUAGGUGAUCCACCCACCUCAGUCUCCCAAAGUGCUGGGAUUAUAGGUGUGAGCCACUAUGCCUGGCCAUAUGCUGUGUUUUCUAACACAGACAACUCCUUUCCACUCCCCUCCAGCCUCAUCCCUUCUGGUCUUCCUGGCAUGGAUAAGGCUGGCCGGGGCACACUCAUAGCACCUUCUGUGUGUCUGCUGCCGCUACUCUUUACCCCUCAGCAUAGUCCUUUCUUAAGCCUGCCCCAAACUCUAAAGAGCGAGGACAGCACUUUUUGCAUUAUUGUUUCCUUGGGGUGUGGCACUCAAUACGUGACCAAUAAAUAGUCAUGGAACACUGAGACUGUGGCACUGGUCUGCAGUCCCUCCUGGGGCCUGGCCCACAAUACUGGGGACUGGGUGGUGGCACAAAGGAAGAAAACGUAUUUACACAAGGCCAGGACGUAAGAGCUUGGGGUGGCCUGCCUUGAACAUGUGAGAAGUCAAGGGGGUUGGUGACUGAGGGAGGGGGGCAGUCUGGUCACUCUUCCUUUUGGCGGGCAAUGUCCUUUGAUCCUUUCACCCAUGGACAAGCUUGGGGAGAAAGGACGUCUCACUGCCAGCGGAGACGAGAUGUCAGAUAGAGAGGCCUGCACCUUGGAGAUUUUCUCGCGAAUAUAACCUGUAAGACAACUGUGCUUUCUGCUGCCUAAUCCAGGAUUCUCUUCAGAGUGCUCUGCCAUCCAUGUUUAAGUUAAUUGGGAUACUGGCUAGCCCAUUUCCUGAAGAUAACACUUUCUUUAAACUUUUUUUUGUGUGUGCGUGUGGGAAAAUGUACAUAACAUAAAAUUAACCAUUUUAAGUGUAUAGUUCAGUGUAAGCCAUUCACAUUGUUGUGCAACCAUCACCACCAUCCAUCUCCAGAUAUUUUUCAUCUUCCCAAGCUGAAGCUAUAUCCCCAUGAAACUAUAACUCAUCCCCACUCACCCCAGCCCCUGGUAACCCCCAUUCUACUUUCUGUGUCUAUGAAUUUAACUACUCCAGGCACCUCGUAUCAGUGGAAUCAUACCAUAUUUGUCUUUUAGUGAUGGCUUAUUUCACUUAGCAUGUCUUCAAGGUUCAUCCAUGUGUAGCAUGUGUCAGAAUUUCCUCCCUUUUGCAGGCUAAAUAAUCCUCCAUCAUGUGCAUGCACCACGUUUUGUUUCUUUGUUCAUCCGUCAGUGAACACUUGAGUUUCUCUCAGCCCUUGGCUACUGUGAAUAGGGCUGCUAUGAACAUGGGUGUACAUAUCUUUGUAUGUCCCUGCUUUUGCUUUUGGGGGGUCUACAGACUAUUUUUUAAAGGAUAACAUAGUGUAAAUCAUCGCCUGCAUACUUCCUAAUCGGCUUGGGCUAAUGGACUUGGGCUAAUGGAGCAACUGUCCUUCCGCAGAGAGGUGGGGACAUGCAGGGCAGUGAUUUGUUCUCAAGGAAGUGGAAUUUUACACAGUUGACUGCUUCUUGUUGUGGUUGACCUUUUGCAGAUCAUUUCCUUAGAGUUUUCAAUGUUUGUCCAUAUCUUACCAAUUAGCAGUUAUAAACUCUUGAGAAGACAGGAAAAUAGUUAUUUUUAUUUUCUUGGAUUAAAGGCAGAAAAACAUUCCUCUGGUUCUUGUGAACAUCCAUUGAUGUGCACGCAUAUCCCCCCUCUCUUCCUUCAGGUAGAUUGUCAGGGGUGACAGGACUGUUGUACCCCAGCCUUUAAAAUCCCAGAAUUUCCACGUGUUAUAAUUUUGCACUGUGUUCACAUAUUAGGUCAUGCAGGGCAAACAAAAUAUACAUGGCAACAUCUCUCCUAUUCUGCAGCCCAGACAUGCCCUUGAAAGUGUGUAGGAGGGAGAGGGUUUCCGAAGCCAAAUACGUUUGAAGAGGGGGCUACAGAGCCCCCUCUUCAGGACUCAUGAUGCACAUUAACAUGCUAAAGGCUCUGAGAAGUCCUGAAAAUGAGACACCAGCUUGACUUUGUUUCACUGAAUGUUAUCGCUAAUUAGCCAGUUACUCCCUUUUUUAGAUGAACACUUAUUGUUACCCUUUUAGGCAUGCUGCCUUCAAAAAAAGCUUCAACUGCUGGCUUAGAAGUGGGUGUGUCUUUCAAAUGCAGCUAGACAGGGAGGAGAGUCCAGUUGUGAAGGGCUUCCUUAUUGGAUCGUUAAUUUUAUUAAUAUAUUUUUACGUUGUCUUUUGCUGUCUAUUUGCCUUUGAGUGAGACAGAAGGAAGAAUUGGGGAAUGCUGAAUGGAUCAACUUGACUGUCCUGUGGCAAGCUUUGUCAAGCCCGCUCUGCUGCAUCAGUAGUGAAUGGAGAGAAUUAUUUUGGCAGGGCUGGGAUGGAGUUCAGGUGCCCUGGCUUGUUACGCAAAGCCAAGCCCAUGAAGCCCGAGACACUGAUUGCAGUUAGUACUACAGCAGAAGGGCCUUCUCAUGUUCAUCCCUGGAGUUCCCCCAAAAGUUCACACCCUCCAAGUCCUGUAAUUCCAACUCCACAAGUAACAGAAGGAUGUCCCCUCAGGAGCUGGCCAUCCGAGGCCUGUCACCAAUAUUAAAACACUGUACCACUCUGAGCAGCCUGGAGGGUGAGGAGGGGCAGGAAGGUCUCUGAUAAGAGACUCUGGUGAGGGCCGCGACUUGGGCAGCUUUGCAGCCUCCUUGGCAUGAGAGGGUCUCUGCUCCCUUUCUCUGUCCACUUACUGAGGCUUGAGUUGUGACAUGUGUUCUCUACUCCUUUCGCUGUCCCAUACGCAUCUGGCCAGGCCCCGGUGAGUUCUCAGGGUAGUGAUCCUGGCUUUGGCCUAAGGAUGCUUUGAGGUUCUAUCUGAGGAAACUCUUAGAGAGCUGCCUCUCAGUCCGCUUGUCCCCAGGAUGCCGGAGGCACUGAAGUGGAAGGUCGGGAGCCUUCCUGGCUCACCCCACCUCGGGUGCAGCCGACCUUCUUCCUCUCCCGACCAGAGGGCGGGGGCCGGGAGCCAGCCUGCACAGUCACACUCUGCUGUCAUGCUGCCAGUUUGGCACGGUGUUUUUAGAAGAUUAAUAGUUAGUUCAAAGGAAGAAAAUAAAAACACACUCUUGGGUGUAAUCGUGUUGUCAGCUUUUGAGAACCAUCCUACUUUUUUUUUUCUUUUGGUCAGAAAAAUAGUAUAUUUAAGGAAUGAUUGCAGGAAGUGUUGGAAACGAAGCUGUUGCUGUUCCCAGGAUGCUGCUGAGGAGGUCAAAGUGAAGGGCACGGCAUCCUGAGAGGUGGUGGGAGGACCUGAAAGCACGGUAGAGCCCCGGGUAGACCUGGACCUGCUCCUCCUUCAGCAUCUCCCAGCUAUGAACACAGCUGCUCCCUGGAGGGCGUCUUCCAUCCUCGUCUGGCCCACUUUCUAAUCUGGUGCUGACUAUGCAGACAGGAUGUAAAACUAGUAAAAUACCCCUUAAUUUGGGUCAGUUAGGGGUGAGGCUAAAAUGAAUAGCUCAGACUCUAAGUAAUCAAAACCCUUUUUGAAGUAGUUUUAUUACUCUCAGAUCCAAAAUGUUACUUACCAACAGACAUAAGCCCCCGAGGACCUGCUUAACUGACAGACAAAAUUAAUGAGUAAUAAUCACUUUGUGCCGGUUACUGCACCAGGCGCAUUCCCGAUGUUAUUUUUGACUCUUGUAACAACCCUCUGGUGAAGGUUUUGCGACUCCUACGUCAUAGAUGUUAAAACUGAGCCCCCACACGGUGAAAAAGCUUGCCCUGAUGACCGCGGGGCGAAACUAGAAAUAAAACUGGGGCUUAUCAGGCUCAAACUCCGAGCUCUUAGCCUGCAUCCCAGCUGUGCUUGACAGCACAUUCGCAAGCUGGCUCAGACCCCACUUUAGGCUCUGAAUUCCAUGCUACCAGGCUCUCGCUUACCAUGCGAUGCCCUUCCUCAGAGACAGUGGUAAGCCAGAGUCCAACCCAAUGAAGACAAAGUCCAAAUGGGUAAAAACCUGAAGGAUUAUGCUGUCCUGUAGCAGCAGUCACACCUACUACAGCUGAGAACUACUAUAGUUGAGUAACUUUGGGAUGUGGAGUAGGCCCAGGGCAGCCUCCAGCUUUGUGUACCUUGUUUGUAGCUGGUUGGUGUUAGCUGUUUUCAUGGAAAAGGUCAUCAUUUAGAUCCACGGUUGUACUGGCUUCUAGUUUGAGCUAAAUAAAGCAAGAAAAAAAAAGAGAAAGAAAGAAAAAGGCAUCAUGUCAUCUUCAAGAUGGUUACACCAGUGUUGAAACAGGAGAAAAACUGGUUUACCAUCUCAGGUACUCUGAUUCAUAUGUUACAGAAAAAGAUGAGUAUUUGGCAGGAAGCCUAAGAGUAGGUCUCAAUUAAAAUGUUAAUUUUUUUUUUUUCCUAAUCCUUCCUGUUGUAAGAGUUUGGGACUAGAAUGAAGGUAGUACCACCACACUGACCAUUAGAUUAGCAGUUGUCCUGGCUUGGCAGUAAUUGACUUGUGAAAUUUGUUGGGAGAGUCAUGCGUCCCUGUGCAUCAGGUCACCCUGUCUGAAAAUGACAUUUUCCACGGCAGUCUGGUAUGGAGCAGCUGAGCCCAAGGAAACCUGGGCUCUGCUCAAGUCUGACUUGGCUAUAAGCUUUUUUAAUUCUGAAUGAGUCACUUCACCUCUUAUUCAGUUUCUUUGUUUUUAAAAUAGGGAGUUGAUCAUAACUUUUUUCAACAUUUCAGUACUAAAAAUUCUAUUUAAAAAAGAUACUGUGAUAUUAGUAUCUUAAACAGCCAUCAUGUAUCAAAUAUCUGCUAUUCACAGACCCCUGACAAAUUAUUAUUUGUUUAGUCACUGUAACAAUGAAAUAACACCGAAGCCUGUCCUGUUUUCAGUAUGCUACUUUGCUUCUAUAUGCACAUAAAGUGUAUUGAAUAUUUGUCCAGACAAAUGCUAUAACCUGUAACAAAUUAAUAUAAACCAGAGAAUUGUAUUUAUUUGUAUGAACUAGGGCUGUUUCUUUGAGUUUACUGGGGGAAAGAACCUGAGUUUCAAUCAGAUACAGAUUUAUAAUUUAUGUAAGAGACACUUGAUCUUGGACUAGCAUCACUUCUCAGCCUCAGUUUCUUCAUCUGUGAAAUGGACAUACUGGUAAUAAUGUCCAUGCAAUGGGCCUGUUGUGCUGUCAGGGUGCUUAGUCAAAGCAGCUGGCAGAGUCCCUAGCACAGGGUAGAUACUUAAUGAAUCUUAGUUUCCUUUCUUCACCUAGAACAAUGCUUAAUUUAAUGUCAUAGAUUUGUUCUAUUAAGAGAUAAUUAUUCGGCCGGGUGCGGUGACUCAUGCCUGUAAUCCCAGCGCUUUGGGAGGCCGAGGUGGGCGGAUCAUGAGGUCAGGAGAUUGAGACCAUCCUGGCUAACACGGUGAAACCCCGUCUCUACUAAAAAUACAAAAAAUUAGCCGGGCGUGGUGGCGGGCGCCUGUAGUCUCAGCUACUCGGGAGGCUGAGGCAGGAGAAUGGUGUGAAUCUGGGAGGCGGAGCUUGCAGUGAGCUGAGAUUGCACCACUGCACUCCAGCCUGGGCAACAGUGAGACUCCAUCUCAAAAAAAAAAAAAAAAAAAGAAUUAUUCAUUGUUUUAAAUAAAUUUUUCAUAUACCCAAUUUUCUACUGGCUUUUAUAAUAAAACUAGAAAUAUCUUUCCCUGGAGGAAAAUUACCAAUAGAGAAAAGUUUGGUGGAAACAUUUAAAAACUAUAUUGCCUAUAUAAAUUUGGUAUAAUAAUUAUGUAUUAAUUAUUUAAAUUAAAUUAUACUUGAAAAAUAAUCACAGAAAGAGGCUUAAGAAGAUAAAUAGCAGAGCACAGUGAACACGGGUGGACACGGGAGCAUUCUGACUUCUGGGAGGGUCAUUCCUACCUGACGUUAACACUCUGCCCCUCCCUCAUUCUGAGCAUUAGCUUAGGCAUGAAGGAAUAAGACAUGGUCCCUUUCUUCAAGGAACUUGCAGCCUAGUGCAGGAGUCAGCAAAAUUUUUCUAAAAAGGGCCACAUAGUAAAUAUUUUUGGCUUUGCAGGCCAUGUGGGCUCUGUUUCAGUUGUUCGACUCUGCCGCUGUAGUGCAGAAUCCGCUGCAAAUGAAUAUAUGAAUGAAGGAGCACGGCUGUGUGCCAAUAAAACUUUAUUUACAAACACAGACAGCAGGGCUGUGUUUGGCCUGUGGGCUACAGAUUGCCACCCCCUGAGCUAGUGGAAGAAAGACUUGUAAACAGGCAAUUAUGAUAUAUUGUAAGAACAGUCUACGUGUUUUAUCAUGAGUACAGGAUGCUUCAGAGGCACAGAUCUCCUGAUCCGGUCUUGGGAGAGGAUACCCCUCAAUGGAGUUUAUUAAACUUUAUAGAAAUAGAGAAGCAUUUUCAUUUGUAAUUUUGUACCCCUUUCCCUUUUCACUUGGUUGUGUGCUUGCGAAAGUAAUAUGUGUUGCUUGAAAGAAAAAAUGCGUGCAGUACAGAAAAUCGGCCAUACUUUGACUGACAGGUGACAUACAAUGUCAAAUCAUUUUGGUUGUGGUGAGGUUUGUCCUUUAAAGCAGGCAUCAAGCCAGAAAAGUUGGAGUGGGAGAAUGAGGGUGUUGUGGGAGUGGGGCACAGAAGAGCAACAUGGGCCAAGGGCAUGGAGGCUCUGGGGAGCUGUGAGCACUUUGGCAAGGCUGGGUCAUGGCAGGGGUUGGGGCAGGAGGUAGUGAUGAGAGAGGUAGGUGGGGGCAGCCACCCCUGGCUCUCUUCCGGAAUUGAUGGCAGCCAGUUUGUACAUGGGAAGAAUAGAAGGUGACAGGUGACUCCAGCCAUAAAGGGAAUGUAACAGGGUCCUGUUACAACAAGGCCAUAGCCUGCGGCUGUGGGAAGCCACUGAGGCAUUUGUUUUCAGCAAGUGGAAGAUGGCUUUCCUUCACCCUCCAAGUUCUCUCCAGGAUGGAUCACCUGGGUCGUUACAGUCUUCUCAUUUCAGAGAUCCCCUGAGGCUCCCAGCAGAAGUUCCCCACCACUGGCUCUCUUCCGGAAUUGAUGGGGACAUCUUAAAUGUUAAUGCUACAGUCCGGCUCUGUUGACACACUGUGUUAUACUAGAAAAUACCCUCCAGUAACACUUGAAACAACUUUUGAAUUUCUCAAGUUAACAGUCUUCAAGUUAUUUCAUAUAAAUGAGUUGCUAGAAGCCUGUGUGCUGACUUCUUGCAGGGCAUUAAUAGCUGCUCCCUUUUGAUGCUAAGGGAUCUGUGGGGUUCCUUCCUUCCUCCCUCCCUCCCUGCAUUCCUCCCCACUCCCUCCUUCCUUUUUAACUUACAGGGCUUACUCUUAAUUUCCUUUCUUAGAGGUAGUUGAUGAGGGCCGUUAAUAAAAUACACAGUGCAGAAUUUGGAAAGACUCUUCAAGGUUUUGGUAGCUAAAAGGGCAUUGCUUAUUAAUUAUCUCUGCUGCUUUGUGGGUAUCUAUUCAGCUUCCCCAAAUGCCAUCGGGGCCCUGUACAAAACGAAUAAGAACGUUCAAUAAUGCAAACCUCUGCUGAGAAAGAUGUACCUCCCUAUUUCCUUCAAGAAAAAGUAAAAGAAACAAACAAAGAAAAGUGACUCAUUGUAUUUUUCCCUCAGAGAUAAUCCUACACAUCACUGAGGAUGUGUUCAGGUGGUAAUUUUUUCUGUUUUUCAAGUUCUACAUCUCUAGCCCUUUAAAAAUGAUCAAAUUCAGUGAGAACCAGGAAAGCCCCAGUGUCAGUAAAUGAAGCAGUUUCUAUUUCUCUCCCACCGGGAAGGCUGCACUGCGCAGAAGAGGAGCGGACAGUAGAGUUGUCAUUUGAAGAAAAAAAGACAAAAAAAAAAAUUGUUGCUUAAGGGUUCGAAUGAAUCGGAAAUUACAUUACUCAUUAAAAUGGGACUACGUGAAGUUUAAGAAAUAUGAGCAGCUUUAACGGUGUGGCUCUGGGGUGGGUUUCCUUAGAGAGGCUCAGAAUGCAGGUCUGCUAGAGUUGGGGUGUAUCUUCCAUCCAGCAGGAAGGGUUUGCAAUCUAUUUUUGCCCCGGCUAUUCCCCUCAAUGUACCAUGGUUAUUAUUUUAGCACUAAGGUAGAAAAAAGGAAAGAUGAGGAGCAAUUUGAGCAGCAAUUAAUAUUCAUUAAAGAACAGAGAAACAAAAUUGAAAAGAGAAAAAAUUUCCCCGGAGUACCCAAGGAUGUUCAUUAUGUCAUUCAAGGAAGCUUGCACCAAUGCCAACUCUAAUUGGCAGUUGUGUUGGCUACUGUUGACAGCAAACCUCCUAAAAUUGGAGGAUGAGCUUAGAGGCAAAAAGUAGAGAGUAAUUUGAGGUUUUCAAGUCAUGCAGUAUAUCUUGAGUUUUGAUGGAAUCUUUUAGGGGAAAAAAAAUCUGUCAACUGUUAGAUUUAAAAUACUGAAAAACACAUUUAGGUAGCAUAGCCUCCCUAAAUGUUGAGAAACUAAUCGUAGCUAAUGUGCUUCAUCAGCCUGGCUUGUGGAGGGUGUUUCUUUUGUCCGUCUGUGACUCAUCUUCCAGGGUGGACUCUGUGUGUGUGUUCUUGCCAUUUCUAUUGUCUGCAGUUAAGAAGUGCAGAGCACCGCACGUCCAUGGUAUAUAAAACACUGGUUCAUGAGAGGCUGCUGAAGCUCUGUUUUAGGGGGGAAAAAUGCUGACCCUACAUUUCUCUAAAUUCCUGCGACCCAGUCAGGAACUUUGUUUUACUUAAGCUUUUGAAGUUUUAAGCAGUACUAUCCUCUUUGUAGGGCUGAACAGAAAUAUUUUCUUUUAUCUCAACUGACACUGCUCAGCUUUAAAACAGACAGUGUGCACAGCGAUUGGUAAAACCCUCGUGGUUUGCUGAUAGAACAAUUUCAAAUGGGGAUCUCCACUACAAAAGAUGAAACUUGGGGGAAAAUUUUCAUUCACUUCCCUAAAAAACACUUUUCGCUUUAGUCAGUGAGCAUUAACGUGCUUAACCUUCAGGCUGUGAAGACGUGGUUUGUUCCCAGUCACUUUCAGAAUAAGCUUCCUGUAGGCCUGAUUUAUAGGAUUGUCUUAAAAUACGUGUUUCCGAGAAGGCGAAAAGGUUUUUCCUUUGUUGGUUUGUUUUUUAAUGAUUUUGUCUUUGCCUCCCCACCAUCGCUACCACUGUGGGAGUUUACAUUAUUUUUCCCUACAUUUUUUUUCUGUCAUUUGAGGGCUUAUAGAUUCAUCGUAGAAAGUUUGGAAAAGUCAAGAAAAGUAUAAAGUUGAAAAUAAAACUCAGUCUUAUUUCUACUCUUUAGAGAUAGUCACUUUAAAAUAUUUUGGAAUAUUUUCUUUUAACUUUUCCUGCAUAUACAAACAUCUCUUCUAGUCACCGUUUUUCCAUUCUGAAGCUUUCAUACAAUUAUAUCAUGAGCAUUUUCCUCGAUCAUUCAUUUUCAAAAGCGAAAUUUUUAAUGGCACUAUGGUAUCAUUGACAUUGAGUCAGGUUCUCAACUUUUGCUCUGAUAAGUUACAAACAGUGAAAAUCAUUGCAUAGAGACCUCUGUGGGUGUCUCUGAUAAUUUACUUGAGAUAAAGUUCCAAGAAAGGGAAUUGCUGGGAUAAAGAGUAGACCCCAUUUAAAGUAAUGUGCUGCAUAUUGCCAAAUUGUCUUCCAGAAAAACAGUGCCUAGUUUAUGCUCCUUGUACAGAUUUGUACCUCUUUGUUUCUCCUUCAUCUUUAGAAAUUUUUUUAAAAUUUUCUUUUUGAAAAACAAAAUAUUGUCUUUUUUUUUCCUUUUCUUUUUUCUUUUUUUUUGAAACAAUGUCUCAUUCUGUCACCCAGGCUGGAGUGCAGUGGCGCAGUCUUGCUCACUGCAGCUUCUGUCUUCCAGGUUCAAGCAAUUCUCAUGCCGUAGGCUCCUGAGUAGCUGGGAUUACAGGCAUGCACCACCACACCCAGCUAAUUUUUGUAUUUUUAGUACAGGAUUUCACCAUAUUGGCCGGGCUGGUCUAGAACUCCUGACCUCAAGUGACCCUCCCACCUUGGCCUCCAAAAGUGCUGGGAUUAUAUGCGUGGGCCACUGCACCUGGCCGUCUUCAUUAGUGAAAUCAAACAUUUCCCAAGUGUUUAACUAUUUGUGUUUCAUAUAUGGUUAAUCAUGUGGGCGCUUAACUCAAUUUCUGGUUGCAGUAUUGGUGUAUAUUGAUAUGUAAGUGGAUAUAUAUUACAAAUUUAGGUCUUUAUAAUUUUGCUUAUUGUAUUUUUGAUGUGUAGAUUUUUAAAAUAGUAAUUAAUAGUAAAGUAGUAAUCAUUAGACUGUUACAAAAUCUACCAGUUGUUUCCUUAGGUAGUUUUUCCCCCUUAGUUUUUCUCUUUGGAGAUUUUAUCUUCACUUCAAAAUUAAAGAAGCAAUCUAUUUGCUUCCAAUUUUUUUAUGUUCUUAUUUUACAUUUUAUCAUAGAAUUCAUUACUGUGGAAAAUAAGGUUGUUUUCUUUAUCUCCCAUUUAUUUUCCAUCUUCUUUAGAAAUUUUCUGAGUCUCCUUGAUGAAUGUUUCUCCACUCUGGCAAGUCAAGCAAUUGAAUUAUUCCUUUCAAAAUAAUAUUAAUGGUAUUUUCUUUAGCUUAUCCUUAAACUAUAUAGGUUCUCUGACUCCACAGUUUUUGGUUUUUUUUUUUUUUUUCUCAUUUUGCUAGAACACAUAGCAACUAACGUGUGUGAAAUGUAGACACACUCUGGAGUCAUUUGUCUCACCACUUAGUCAUGGCUCAGAAGCGUCACAUGGCAUCAUCAUGAAUGUCCCUGGUCUUGGAAAAAUGACAAAGCAAGCAAGCCUAAGAUUAUGAAAUGAGGCUGUGACUUUAGUGCUUUUAUGAUCUUGUUAAACCUGCUGAUGAGGUGUUAACAAGCUUAAUUAAAGGAUGCUUUUCAUUGUUCUGUAGGGAAUGGAUUUGAGGGAGGUUAGAGUUAAUGCAGAGAGACUCUUGUAUUAGUUCAGGAGAGGGAGGAUGGAUGGUGACUUGGCCUUAUCUUGUCUGCUUACCCCCUGCAAAUUCCAUCCCAAGGAAAUUUGACCAGAGAACAAGGUUCAAUUUGCAAAUGACAGAAGCCACUCUGGUAUUUCAGGAGAUAGGGACUGAAUACAGGGAAUAGUGCUUACUGAGUUGCUAGAGCAACUGUAAACGGGCCUCUGGAAGGAUUCCUGGCAGAGCUAGCCUGUCCAGGGAACUGUGCCUCCAUUAGGAGGCUGAAGAAUUAGAAGGUCACUGUCCCAACCACUGGUUCCAAGAUCACACCUCCUUAGCCACCUCCAGAACUGUUGGCUCCCAGACCACCCAACCCUUGCCAGAGCUGACCAGCAAAAUGGAUGCCUCCCUUCCUCCCCUCUGAACUCUCUUCCUAACUCAGGUCAGCCGGAAAUUCGAACAAGGUUGCACACAGAAAGUUAUUUUGGGGUGUGCACCUGAUUGGCAGGACCAAAAUCACAUUUGAAACCAUAGGUAUACCAGAAUCUGGAAGUAUGAUUUUUGGCCUCCCAGCCCACACUAUAGGAAGCCCACACCAGAAGGAGACUGGAAUCACAUGAGUGAGCGCCUGCCCCAUCCCUAUAAAUCGGGGUGUCUGUGGGGGCAAUGGAGCACGGAUGGGAUGUUCAGGAUAUAUGUGAAAGGCAGAACCUGCUGGAAUUGGUGAUUGAUUUGAUGGGGAGGGAGGUGACUAGGGUAACGUCAGAGACAAAACCCGUUACAUUCAGUUCUGGUUUUGUACUUUUUAUAACGUUACUCCUGUUAUAUAUUUCUUUAAUCUGAAAAGUUAUAAAUUGCUUUAAACAUUGCUUACCCAACUGGUCAGUGACAUGACCAGUUGCCAUAUCUUAUCUAGAGCAAUGUGAACAAAUUUCAAGAGCCAGGUGACCUCAAAGCUUCCUCAUACUUCUGAAAUUCUUUAGGAGAUUAUACUGUGUCUGAACAUAUUUUCUUUUCCCGACACAUUUUUGUCAAUACCAGAAGCAGAAGUCAAACAAGGGUGUCGGUGCCAUGGGUUCCCCCAGCGCUACCCUACCCUGCUAAACGGCGGUGCCUCCAGGAUGGCAAGGGCGGUGUUGCAGGCGGAUCCCCAGGCAUGAGUAACCCUUAUCAUGGUAAACUUGCUGGGCCUGGGAAUCCAGUUGGUUUACUUGUUGCUUCAGAUAUGCUGUCUAUUCUUGUGCCUAGUUGAGGAGGGUUUAAGGUAGCAGGUGGCUGCCUUGCUCUGGGUUUCCUGCACCCCCUCCCCAGGGGGAAGCCCAGAGGCUGGGAACUGUGGAGCCAGCAAUACUUCUAACCAGGCUUCCUCUCCCUACCAGGCGUGUGAGUGACUCAGUCUCCCUCCACUGUGUUCAUUUUCCACUGUGGCACUGUUAAUGGAUAGGGCUGAUCACUGAAUGUCUUAUUAGCUAGCACCUUAAUGGGGUCAUGGCUGCCCAAGGCCAGGUCUGGUCAUUGCUCAGGUGGCUGAACUCACAACAGUAUUGGCAAUUUCCUCCAGUCCCCUAAAUGCUUUAUUAAAAUUUCUUCUGCCUCCUGGCCAUCUCAUAGAAGCAUAAUAUACUCAUUUGCAUCCUUUAACCUCAAGUAAACUCAUCAAUGGGAAGUCUUGGGGGAGACAUGAAAGCAUUUCAGAUGACUCCCUGCCAUCAAGACAGCAGCUGGUGCCCUUCUCCCCGGCAGCAACCUGGGGUCGGGAUGUGUUCCUCUCCUGCCAAGAUUGUGCCCGACUGAGGCUCCCAAAGGCAUGAUGCAACUGGGAGAUGAGUGGUUACAGGUGUUGAGAGCACCUCCUCUCCCAGAGUGUAUAAACCAAGCUGGAAAAACAGAAUGUGCACCCACUGUGAUUUAUGAAGCUGUCACUCACGUUUUAAGGCAAAACCUGUAUUCCUGAAGUUAGAAAUAGGUUGUGUGGUGAAAGGUUUUUAUUAUCAAAAAUACAUUUUUUCCUAGAAACAGCAUACAUAUGUGAAUGUUCGUUUUCCAGGCUUGCCUCCAAAAGCUCACUGAACUCAUCACCUAGCUGUACGACCCUGCAUUUGCAGAGCAGAGCAGCAGCAGCCAGUAGUCUUUUGCAUGGUUCCCACAGCGUUUUUGCUUCUCCCUGCUCUUGGGAGUUGUUUGAACCCCAGCCCAAGACAGUGAAGCUCAUUCAUUGUCUUCAAAAUGGCAGGGCAGUGUUGGCCAGUAGUUCUCAGAGUCGCAGGGCAGGUUUGCCGAACCACACUGCUGUGCUUACCUGCAGGAGUCUUCAUUCAGUGGGCCUGGGAUGGGGCCCAAGAACUUGCCUUUUCUAACUAGUCCCCAGGUGGUGCUGAUGCUGCUGGUCCCUGGAGCAGUUUGAGGACCACUGGAGCAAUCAUGGAAGGAAGUUAACCCUGUAAGGAGCUCCUGUGUCUGAAUUCUUAAGAAUCUGUGCAACCAGCAGUGCCCUUCUCCCCAAAUUCAUGAAUAAACCCUGACAACAGCAAA